GUAGUGACUCAUCUCGGGCAGAGCGCUAGGGCUCCGAGCGAACCAGCGAGCGAGCGAACGAGCGGCGCUCGGCGGGGACAGAAAGAGGGAGAGAGAGAGAGAGAGAGAGGGAGAGGCGCGGCCGGGCGAGGCGGGCCCGUCCGGGAGCGGGCUCCGGGGAAGGGGUGCGGGUCUGGGCGCCGGAGCGGGGAGCGGGGCCGCGUCCCUCUCAGCGCCAGCUCUACUUGAGCCCCACGAGCCGCUGUCCCCCUGGCGCGCUCGGGGCCGCGGGACGGGCGCACGCCGCCUUCUCCUAGUCAAGUAUCCGAGCCGCCCCGAAACUCGGGCGGCGAGUCGGCCACGGGAAGUUUAUUCUCCGGCUCCUUUUCUAAAAGGAAGAAACAGAAGUUUCUCCCAGCGGACAGCUUUUCUUUCCGCCUUUUUGGCCCUGUCUGAAAUCGGGGGUCCCCAGGGCUGGCAGGCCAGGCUCGCUGGGCUCCUAAUCUUUUUUUUAAUUUCCAAUUUUUGAUUGGGCCGUGGGUCCCCGCUGAGCUCCGGCUGCGCGCGGGGGCGGGAGGGCGCGCGCAGGGGAGGGACCGAGAGACGCGCCGACUUUUUAGAGGGAGGGAUCGGGUGGACAACUGGUCCCGCGGCGCUCGCAGAGCCGGAAAGAAGUGCUGUAAGGGACGCUCGGGGGACGCUGUUCCUGAGGUGUCGCCGCCUCCCUGUCCUCGCCCUCCGCGGUGGGGGAGAAACCCAGGAGCGAAGCCCAGAGCCCGCGGCGCGGCCGGCGGACGAACGAGCGCGCAGCAGCCGGUGCGCGGCCGCGGCGAGGGCGGGGGAAGAAAAACACCCUGUUUCCUCUCCGGCCCCCACCGCGGAUCAUGUACCAGGAUUAUCCCGGGAACUUUGACACCUCGUCCCGGGGCAGCAGCGGCUCUCCUGCGCACGCCGAGUCCUACUCCAGCGGCGGCGGCGGCCAGCAGAAAUUCCGGGUAGAUAUGCCUGGCUCAGGCAGUGCAUUCAUCCCCACCAUCAACGCCAUCACGACCAGCCAGGACCUGCAGUGGAUGGUGCAGCCCACAGUGAUCACCUCCAUGUCCAACCCAUACCCUCGCUCGCACCCCUACAGCCCCCUGCCGGGCCUGGCCUCUGUCCCUGGACACAUGGCCCUCCCAAGACCUGGCGUGAUCAAGACCAUUGGCACCACCGUGGGCCGCAGGAGGAGAGAUGAGCAGCUGUCUCCUGAAGAGGAGGAGAAGCGUCGCAUCCGGCGGGAGAGGAACAAGCUGGCUGCAGCCAAGUGCCGGAACCGACGCCGGGAGCUGACAGAGAAGCUGCAGGCGGAAGCCUCUCAGAAGCUCAUGACGUUCGUCAGACCCUUGAGACAGACGGAAACUGUUUUUCACUCCGGAAUAUGCUGUCCUCUGCUGAACGAAGCCCUUGCCCGAGACAGAGGAGCUGGAGGAGGAGAAGUCAGGCCUGCAGAAGGAGAUUGCUGAGCUGCAGAAGGAGAAGGAGAAGCUGGAGUUCAUGUUGGUGGCUCACGGCCCAGUGUGCAAGAUUAGCCCCGAGGAGCGCCGAUCGCCCCCAGCCCCUGGGCUGCAGCCCAUGCGCAGUGGGGGUGGCUCGGUGGGCGCUGUAGUGGUGAAACAGGAGCCCCUGGAAGAGGACAGCCCCUCGUCCUCGUCGGCGGGGCUGGACAAGGCCCAGCGCUCUGUCAUCAAGCCCAUCAGCAUUGCUGGGGGCUUCUACGGUGAGGAGCCCCUGCACACCCCCAUCGUGGUGACCUCCACACCUGCUGUCACUCCGGGCACCUCGAACCUCGUCUUCACCUAUCCUAGCGUCCUGGAGCAGGAGUCACCCGCAUCUCCCUCCGAAUCCUGCUCCAAGGCUCACCGCAGAAGCAGUAGCAGCGGGGACCAAUCAUCAGACUCCUUGAACUCCCCCACUCUGCUGGCUCUGUAACCCAGUGCACCUCCCUCCCCAGCUCCGGAGGGGGUCCUCCUCGCUCCUCCUUCCCAGGGACCAGCACCUUCAAGCGCUCCAGGGCCGUGAGGGCAAGAGGGGGACCUGCCACCAGGGAGCUUCCUGGCUCUGGGGGACCCAGGUGGGACUUAGCAGUGAGUAUUGGAAGACUUGGGUUGAUCUCUUAGAAGCCAUGGGACCUCCUCCCUCAUUCAUCUUGCAAGCAAAUCCCAUUUCUUGAAAAGCCUUGGAGAACUCGGUUUGGUAGACUUGGACAUCUCUCUGGCUUCUGAAGAGCCUGAAGCUGGCCUGGACCAUUCCUGUCCCUUUGUUACCAUACUGUCUCUGGAGUGAUGGUGUCCUUCCCUGCCCCACCACGCAUGCUCAGUGCCUUUUGGUUUCACCUUCCCUCGACUUGACCCUUUCCUCCCCCAGCGUCAGUUUCACUCCCUCUUGGUUUUUAUCAAAUUUGCCAUGACAUUUCAUCUGGGUGGUCUGAAUAUUAAAGCUCUUCAUUUCUGGAGAUGGGGCAGCAGGUGGCUCUUCUGCUGGGGCUGACUUGUCCAGAAGGGGACAAAGUGCAAUACAGAGCCUUCCCUACCCUGACGCCUCCCAGUCAUCAUCUCCAGAACUCCCAGCGGGGCUCCCUGAGCUCUCAAGGAGAUGCUGCCAUCACUGGGAGGCUCAGAGGACCCUUCCUGCCCACCUUCGGAGACGGCUUCUGGAGGAACGGCUUGGCCAGAAGACAGGGUGUGAGUGAGACAGUGGGGCACAGGUUGGGUUUGCCAAACGCCUAAUUACCAGGCCAGGAAGCAUGCCAACAAAGCCACACGGGUGUCCUAGCCAGCUUCCCUUCACCUGGUGUCUUGAGUAGGGCGUCUCCUGUAAUUACUGCCUUGCCAUUCUGCCCCUGGACCCUUCUCUCCGGACCAGGGAGGCGUCCCUCCCUAGGAGCCACACAUUAUACUCCAAGUCCCUGCCGGGCUCCGCCUUUCCCCCACCCUGGCUCUCAGGGUGACGCCACCCACAGAGAUUUAAUGAGCGUGGGCCUGGACCUUCCCCAGAUGCUGCCAGGCAGCCCCUCCCCAAGCCUCAAAGAAGCAUUUGCUGAGGAUGGAGAGGCAGGGGAGGGAGGCGGGAGGCCGUCACUGGAGUGGCGUCUGCAGCAGCUGCUGCCCCAGCACCCGCUCAGCCUGUCCUGGCUGCUCACCUCCCCGCAGGGCACCGGGCCUUUCCUGCCCUCUGUGGUCAUCUGCCACCUGCUGGAUCAAGUGCUUUCUCUUUUACACUCCCCUGUCCCCACCCCAGUGCACUCUUCUGGCCCAGGCAGCAAGCAAGCUGUGAACAGCUGGCCUGAGCUGUCGCUGUGGCUUGUGGCUCAUGCGCCAUUCCUGGUUGUCUGUUGAAUCUUUCUGGCUGCUGGAAUUGGAGAUAGGAUGUUUUGCUUCCCACUGCAGGAGAGCUGCCCCCUUUCACGGGGUUGGGGAAGGGUCCCCCUGGCCUCCAGCAGGAGCACAGCUCAGCAGGGUCCCUGCUGCCCACCCCUCUGAGCCUUUUCUCCCCAGGGUAUGGCUCCUGCUGAGUUUCUUGUCCAGCAGGGCCUUGACAGGAAUCCAGGGAGUAGCUCCUGGCCAGAACCAGCCUCUGCGGGGCUUGUGCUCUGCAAAGACUCUGCUGCUGGGGAUUCAGCUCUAGAGGUCACAGUAUCCUCGUUUGAAAGAUAAUUAAGAUCCCCCGUGGAGAAAGCAGUGACACAUUCACACAGCUGUUCCCUCGCAUGUUAUUUCAUGAACAUGACCUGUUUUCGUGCACUAGACACACAGAGUGGAACAGCCGUAUGCUUAAAGUACAUGGGCCAGUGGGACUGGAAGUGACCUGUACAAGUGAUGCAGAAAGGAGGGUUUCAAAGAAAAAGGAUUUUGUUUAAAAUACUUUAAAAAUGUUAUUUCCUGCAUCCCUUGGCUGUGAUGCCCCUCUCCCGAUUUCCCAGGGGCUCUGGGAGGGACCCUUCUAAGAAGAUUGGGCAGUUGGGUUUCUGGCUUGAGAUGAAUCCAAGCAGCAGAAUGAGCCAGGAGUAGCAGGAGAUGGGCAAAGAAAACUGGGGUGCACUCAGCUCUCACAGGGGUAAUCAUCUCAAGUGGUAUUUGUAGCCAAGUGGGAGCUAUUUUCUUUUUUGUGCAUAUAGAUAUUUCUUAAAUGAAGCUGCUUUCUUGUCUUUUAUUUCUAAAAGCCCCCUUAUACCCCACUUUGUGCAGCAAAGAUCCCCGUGCAGGUCACAGCCUGAUUUGUGGCCAGGCUGGACAAAUUCCUGAGGCACAACUUGGCUUCAGUUCAGAUUUCAAGCUGUGUUGGUGUUGGGACCAGCAGAAGGCAAACGUCCAGCCAACACACAGGACUGUAAGAGGACUCUGAGCUACGUGCCCUGUGAAGACCCCCAGGCUUUGUCAUAGGAGGUCGUUCAGCUUCCCCAAAGUCAGAGGUGAUUUGAUUUGGGGAAGACUGAAUAUUCACACCUAAGUCGUGAGCAUAUCCUGAGUUUUACUUCCUUAUGGCUUGCCCUCCAAGUUCUCUCUCUCAUACACACACACACCCUUGCUCCAGAAUCACCAGACACCUCCAUGGCUCCAGCUAUGGGAACAGCUGCAUUGGGGCUGCCUUUCUGUUUGGCUUAGGAACUUCUGUGCUUCUUGUGGCUCCACUCGCGAGGCAGCUCGGAGGUGUGGACUCCGAUUGGGCUGCAGGCAGCUCUGGGACGGCACAGGGCGGGCGCUCUGAUCAGCUCGUGUAAAACACACCGUCUUCUUGGCCUCCUGGCCAGUCUUUCUGCGAAUAGUCCUCUCCCUGGCCAGUUGAAUGGGGGAAGCUGCUGGCACAGGAAGGAGAGGCGAUCCCGGCUGAGGCUUAGGAAAUUGCUGGAGCCGGCUCCAAGCAGAUAAUUCACUGGGGAGGUUUUCAGAGUCAAACAUCAUUCUGCCUGUGUUGGGGGCCAGGUGUGUCACACAAGCAUCUCAAAGUCAAAAGCCAUCUGGGGCUGCUGCUUCUGUUUCUCAGGCUCUGGGGAAAGGAAUCUCCCUCUCCUCUCACUUGAUUCCAAGUGUGGUUGAAUUGUCUGGAGCACUGGGACUUUUUUUCUCUUUUCCUUGAUGGACCAACAGUGCAAAUGCAAUCUCGCCAUUUAACUUUCAGGUCGAUUUCCUUUCCUGAUCAGACAUCUUUGUGCCCCCUUUAGGAAGGAAAAGAAUACACCUACGAUGUGCCAGGCACUGUGUUAGGCGCUUUUAUAUAGAUCCUCGUUAGGAUGAGACUAAGGGAUGAGGACAUCUCUUUAUAAAAGGCCCCUAAGUAAUGGAUAAACAGAAACACUUAGAGGUGAGAAGGUCUGUCUUCAAGAUCCAAGGUAAGAUUGCCUUCAGUCUGAUGUUUGUUCUCAAGGACUUAUCCCCUACAAUAUUCUCCCACUCCAUACUUCUCCUUCUACCCCACCAUGUGCUCCCGUGCACUCCUCAGAUGGUCAGAGGGGUAACCCAAGUCCUUAGAGAAUUUGGGGACCAAUAGAAUAUGUGAUGUGUGAAUUUUCUUUAAAAAACUUAAGGAGUCUUUGCUACCUUCUGCUUGUUGAGUUGUUUUGGCAUUCAUAUUAAAAGCCAGCAUCUCACUAUUUAUUGACAGGUUGGGCUGUGUGUGUGCGCAUGUGUGUAUACAUUUCCAGGCGUGCCUGUGUCCUGUAGCUUUUUAAAAGGAAACCCAGUCAUCCCACUAUGAAUCUGGCAUCUUCUUAUGCUUCUAGUGUUUUGGCCAUACAUCAACCAAGGGGUUUAAUUUAUCCAAUGCUUGACGACAUGUUCAGGAGGGGCUGGAUCAAAUUUUGAGAGGGUUAUGGGAAAGGGAGGGGGAGAAGAAAUUGACAUUUAUUUUAUUAUUUAUUUUAAAUGUUUACAUCUUCUUUAUGUUGUAUCAAGCCUGAAUAGAAACUGAUAGCAUUAAAAUACUCCGUUCCUCUCUCUCUUCUCGCUUCCUUUUUUUUUUUUUUUUUAAAUUUAGGAUAACACAUUUUUGUUUCUAAAGUGAUUUGUGAUUUGUGCUGUAUAAACUGUAUAAAAGGUUCUGUUUUUAAAGGUGGAUUUUCAUUCCUCUGGGGACAGUGGUCGCCAAGACAUCUACAUUGUAAGAGAACACAGUGGAAGAUCCUGUCCUGAUUCUCAAAAAUUAUUUUCUCUGUAUGAUUAAAAGUUUAUUCCAUUUAUUUUAGUUUGUGUUUACUUGAUUUUGAGGAAGAAAAUAUUUGACUUUGUGUAAAGAGUAGGGUAUCAGGGUGUCUUUUCUGCCGUGGGAGAUGUGUAUAUAUAUAGUAUUUUGGUGUAUAGUAGAAAAUAAGCUUUGUGCAUCUGUAUUUGAGAUAUGUUAAUGACGUGGAGUAAAGUCAGCUGUAAGACUCUGGAGGCAAACAAGUUGUAUAUGGUUCAUAUGGCUCUAUGGGGAAUUUAAUUACCUUUCUGGGCACUUUUUUUUUUUUUUUUUUUUUAAGUAAUGGUGAAAUGGUCCCAUUGGAGAGUCUCCUAAAUAGACCUUCCAGGCAGAACCGCAAGCUCAAAAUCUUUGUAUAGUUUUGAAAAUUGAGGAGUAGCUUUGUUUGGAAGCCUUUCUGGUGGUGGUUUUUGUUGUUGUUGUUGUUUUGUUGUUUUACUAUAUGUAAUACAAGCCUACAGUAUUUGCACUAAAGAAAGCUUGUUAGAAAAAGCUUGCUGCUAUGGAAGAAAGAACAUAUUAAAACUUCUUUCCCUUGCGAUUUUUUUGGGGGAGGGGGGUUAGCAUUUCCACUUUCAGUUGAGUAGCAUUUUGUAGAAUAAAAUGAAUUAAGAUUGAAGAGCC